AGUGUGCCACCGCCAUCUUUACCGGCUGUGGCUCAGCAUGGUCAGUGCCGUUUAACCUUUAUUGUGGUGGAGUCCACCCCGCUGUGGGCCUCAGAUAACCCUGUACAAAGGGGAAUGGAGAUUGCCUGUAUCCACCUAGAUUCAUAAGCUGCCCUGAGGCGAUCUUGGCAUCAAGAAAGACAGCAUUGAGGCACAUCUCACCAUCAGCUUCAGAGGAUGUCAGCCUUUGAUAUGUCCCAUGGGUUUUUUCCCAGGGAACCAAUCUGUCCUUUUGAAGAAAAGACAAAGAUAGGAACGAUGGUAGAGGACCACCGGUCAAAUUCUUACCAGGAUUCAGUGACGUUUGAUGAUGUGGCUGUGGAGUUCACCCCAGAGGAGUGGGCUUUACUGGACACAACUCAGAAAUACCUCUACAGAGAUGUGAUGCUGGAGAACUACAUGAACCUGGCCUCUGUGGAUUUCUUUUUCUGCUUAACUUCAGAAUGGGAAAUACAACCUAGAACCAAACGGUCAUCACUUCAGCAGGGUUUUUUGAAGAAUCAAAUAUUCACUGGGAUACAAAUGCAGACAAGAAGCUACAGUGGAUGGAAACUCUGUGAGAAUUGUGGAGAGGUCUUCAGUGAACAGUUUUGCCUUAAGACACACAUGAGAGCUCAGAAUGGAGGGAACACUUUUGAGGGUAAUUGUUAUGGAAAAGACAGCAUCAGUGUGCACAAGGAAGCCUCUAUUGGACAAGAACUUUCCAAAUUUAAUCCAUGUGGAAAAGUCUUCACCUUAACUCCAGGCCUUGCUGUGCAUCUUGAAAUUCUCAAUGGAAGACAACCCUACAAAUGUAAGGAAUGUGGAAAAGGCUUUAAGUAUUUUGCAAGCCUUGAUAAUCACAUGGGAAUCCACAUUGGAGAGAAACUCUGUGAAUUUCAGGAAUGUGAGAGAGCCAUCACAACUUCCUCACACUUAAAGCAGUGUGUAGCAGUUCAUACUGGAAAGAAAUCCGAAAAGACUAAGAACUGUGGGAAAUCCUUCACUAAUUUUUCUCAACUUUCUGCACAUGCAAAAACUCAUAAAGGAGAGAAGUCCUUUGAAUGUAAAGAAUGUGGAAGAUCCUUUAGAAAUUCCUCAUCCUUUAAUGUUCACAUUCAAAUUCACACUGGAAUAAAACCACACAAAUGUACGGAAUGUGGGAAAGCCUUCACUAGAUCAACUCACCUUACUCAACAUGUAAGAACUCACACUGGAAUAAAACCCUAUGAAUGUAAGGAAUGUGGCCAAGCCUUCACUCAGUACACGGGCCUUGCUAUACACAUACGAAAUCACACUGGAGAGAAACCCUAUCAGUGUAAGGAAUGUGGGAAAGCCUUCAAUAGAUCUUCAACGCUUACUCAACAUAGAAGAAUUCACACAGGAGAGAAGCCUUAUGAAUGUGUUGAAUGUGGGAAGACCUUCAUUACUUCUUCCCAUCGUAGUAAACAUUUGAAAACUCACAGUGGAGAAAGGUAAAUGCAAGAUAUGUGGGAAAGAAUUUCUGUAUUCCUCACCCCACCUGUGAACUCCUACCAGAGAGAAACCUUUUGUAUGUAAAGAAUUUGGGAAAGCAUUUGCUCUUUCCUCAUGCCUAAGUAUGCAUGAAAGAAUUCACACUGGGGAGAAAUACUAUGAAUGUAAGGAUAUGAGUGUUGUUACCAUUUAGCCCAUUGGUUGCCAUCUUUAAUUAUUGGCAGUGCAAAGAUCAUCAGAUUAGUCCUAAAUGCCUUUUGGAGGUUGUAAUGGCUCACAGAUUGGCCUUAGAUGCAUCCCGAGGGUCUGAAAUUAAACCUACAGGUUCUGAAUACAACAUCAUGGUUACCUGAGUCUGGGCAUCUGUGAAGAAGGGUCAUGGAUGGUGAGGUCAGUACUGCAGGCUGCCUCACCUUGGUGAUUAGAUUCCUAAGAUCAUAGCAUUAACAAGUUCUGUACGAGAUAAAUCAUGCAGAUUGAUCCCAGCCCCUGUUGGUUAGUGGCUGCCAGUGUGGCACAUUCAUGUCAAAAUUUACCAGAAGCCAAGAUGAUGUAGGCCCCAGAGGUGGAUUGUUAAAAAGAUGCUCCUCCAAGGUUCUCUUCUGUUCCCAUGGAUCCUGCAGAGCAUGUCAGGAGUGAAACCAUCCAUAACUGCCAGUGCCCUUUCACAGCUGAUUAUUUCUAUGUCCCCUUCUUGUAAAAUAAGAAGUGUGACAACCUUGACUGUUCUGUUCUGUCUUCUCUGUCCAUUUUAGGUGGCACAAUGUAAGUGGCAGUGUCUCUUAUAGUAUAAUCCAGUCUCUCUUCUCACUUCUGUUAAGAUGGCUGAUAUAGUCCAUGAAUCCCACUCAUGAUCUCUUUAUCAAAUGAUUGUUCAGCCACACUUUGAGGAUUCUCUUCAGUACAAGUUUUCUAAUUUUUGCAGUAUGGAUAGGCUGAGAAUUUUCCAAAUCUCCAAGUUCUGGUUCCUUUUUCCUUAACAAUUUCUUCUGCAAUUCAGGUCUCCUUUUGCAUUUUUGCCGAGACCAGCUGGGUCGUGGAGACCCUAACCCAGUGGCUCUAGAGGAAUUAAGACAAAGACACAGAAAUAUAGUGCAGAGUGGGAAUCGGGGCUCACAGCCUUCAGAGCUGAGCUUGAACAGAGUUUGACCCACAUAUUUAUUGACAGUAAGCCUGUGAUAAACAUUAUUCCUAUAGAUUGUAGAUCAGCUAUAAGUAUUCCUUAUGAGAAAGAAAGGGACAGGCUCUGGCUUGUUAUCUGCAACAGGAAUAUGUCCUUAAGGCACAAAUCACUCAUGCUAUUGUUUGUGGUUUAGGAAUGCCUUGAGCAGUUUUCCAGUUUUCUGCCCUGGGUGGGCCAGGUGUUGCUUGCCCUCAUUCUGGUAAACCAGCAGCCUCCAGCAUGGGCGUCAUAGCCAUCACGAGCAUGUCACAGUGCUGCAGAGAUUUUGUUUAUGGCCAGUUUCUCAUUGCCUGUUUAUGGCCAGAUUUGGGGGGCCUGUUCCCAGCACAUUUUCCUGUAAGCACUCAGGAAUAAUGAAGCUUCCUGUGUCCUUUAACACUUUAAUUACAGAUCUUAGUGAUACAUACCAUUUUAUCUGUCUCAAGCUCUACCUUCCGUAAAAUGCUAGAAUACAGUUCUGCCAAGUUCUUCACCACUUUAUAUCAAGGGUUGUCUUUUCUUCAUUUCCCAAUAGCAUGUUCCUCAUUCCCCAAUGACACCUCACCAGAAUAACCCUUACCAACCUUAUUUCCAGCUUGCACAUCAGAAUUUUUCCAGCCUCUACUCAUUUGUCAGUUUCAAAGCUGCUUCACAUUUUUAGUUUUUUUGUUUGUUUUUAAUUGCAGUACCUCACUUCUCAGUACCAAUAUCUGCCUUAGUCAGCUCAGACAACCAUAAGAGAAUACCGCAGACCAAAUGGCUUAGAAAUUAAUUUAAUUUUAAAUCAAUGAGGUUAAAAACACAGGAUUUUUUUUUUUUUUUUUUUUUUUUUUUUGAGAUGGAGUUUUGCUCUUGUUGCCCAGGCUGGAGUGCAAUGGUAUGAUCUUGGCUCACCGCAACCUCCACCUCCUGAGUUCCAGUGAUUCUCCUGCCUCACCCUCAGUAGCUGGGAUUAUUGGCAUGCACCACAAACCUUAGCUAAGUUUGUAUUUUUAGUAGAGACAGGGUUUCUCCAUGUUGGUUAGGCUGAUCUCCAUGUUGGUCAGAUCUGACCUUUGGUGAUCCACCUGCCUUGGCCUCCCAAAGUGCUGGGAUUACAGGCCUGAGCCACCGUAUCUGGCCCAAAACACAAAUUUAUAUUCUCACAUAUCUGGAGGCUGGAAGUCUGAGAUCAGAGUGCCAGCAUGGUCAACCUCUAGUGAGAGCUCUCUUCCUGGCAUGUAAGUGCCCACUUCCUCAUGUUUUCACACGAUGGAGACCAACAAAUAGGUCGGUCGGUCUCCCCCCUCCCCGCCCCCUUCUCUUUUCACAUACAGUCACAUUGAGGUUUGGAACUUCAUAUGAAAUUUGGGGGGUCACUGUGUGUGUGUGUGUGUGUGUGUGUAUGUGUAUAUAUAUAUACAUAUAUAUACACAUAUGUAUGUAUACCUAACUCCUAAAGUGGAACAGUAAGAGUCAUUAUUUAUAGAUUAUCUGAUUCUCUAUGUGGAAAGAGAAAAGAAUCAUAUUAAGUACUUUGGACUGAACAAUGACCCCCAAAAUUCGUAUGAUGAUGAAGCUCUCUCUAAAUAUUUUCUUGCUUUACUGGACUGAUUUUAACCCGCUGCACAACACCAACUAAAAGUAGUAAUACCAGCAUACUUGUCUUUGCAGUUCUGGUGAGAUAUGCACUCUAUUUUGUUGGUUUGGCUGUAGGCUUUUAUUUCUUUUUUAUUUUUUGAAGAGGUUAUGUCCUGUCAGGGAACCAGCCCCGAUAUUCACAUAGGUUCUUUUCUAUUUUCCCUAAGUGUCAGCCAACUUGAGAAAUAAAGGGACAGAGUACAAAAGAGAGAAAUUUUAAAGCUGGGUGUCCGGGGCAGACAUCACAUGUCGGUAGGUUCCGUGAUGCCCCACAAGCCGCAAAAACCAGCAAGUUUUUAUUAGGGAUUUUCAAAAGGGGAGGGAGUGUGCAAAUAGGUGUGGGUCACAGACAUCAAGUACUUUACAAGGUAAUAGAAUAUCACAAGGCAAGUGGAGGCAGGGCGAGAUCACAGGACCAAGGUGAAAUUAAAAUUGCUAAUGAAGUUUUGGGCACCAUUGUCAUUGAUAACAUCUUAUCAGGAGACGGUUUUGAGAUCAACUGGUCUGACUAAAAUUUAUUAGGUGGGAAUUUCCUCUUCCUAAUAAGCCUGGGAGUGCUAUGGGAGACUGGGGUCUAUUUCACCCCUGCAGUCUCGACCAUAAGAGAUGGCUACACCCAGGGGGGCCAGUUCAGAGACCCACUCCCAGGUGUGCAUUCUCUUUCUCAAGGAUGUUCCUUGCUGAGAAAAAGAAUUCAGUGAUAUUUCUCCCAUUUGCUUGUGAAAGAAGAGAAAUGUGGCUUUGUUCCACCUGGCUCACCGGCGGUCAGAAUUUAAGGUUAUCUCUCUUGUUUCCUAAACAUUGCUGUUAUCCUGUUCUUUUUUCAAGGUGCCCAGAUUUCAUAUUGCUCAAACACACAUGCUGUAUAAUUUGUGCAGUUAAUGCAAUUAUUACAGGGUCCUGAGGUAAUAUACAUCCUCCUCAGCUGACAGGAUUGAGAGAUUAAAGUAAAGACAGGCAUAGGAAAUCACAAGGGUAUUGACUGGGGAAGUGAUAAGUGUCCAUGAAAUCUUUACAAUUUAUGUUUAGAGAUUGCAGUAAAGACAGGCAUAAGAAAUUAUAAAAGUAUUAAUUUGGGGAACUAAUAAAUGUCCAUGAAACCUUCACAAUCCAUGUUUUUCUGCCAUGGCUUCAGCCAGUCCCCCCGUUUGGGGUCCCUGACUUCCUGCAACAAUGUCCUGCAGGAAAAGUUUUUUCUUUAUAUCCAGUUUUUACAUGAUGAAUUAUUUCCCAAUAUUUCAUAGUUUAUGAGGCUGAAUUCCUCUUGAAUUUAUUAAAUGCUUCCUUCACAUCCUCUGUGAUGAUCAUGUUUAUUUACUGAUAAAACUCAAUACCUAGAACUGCACCUAGCUCAUGAUGGUACCUAAUAAAUACUUCAAUGAAAUGAUGUGGUGAUGCAUGCCUAUAGUUUUAGCUACUUGGGAGGGUGGCCUGAGCCCAGGGGUUCUAGACCAGCUUAGGCAACAUAGCAAGACCCCAUCUCAAAAAAAAAAACAAAAACAAAACAAAAAAAAAACUUGAAGAAGUGAAUGCAUGGAAAGGCGCUUUUCUAAAACAAAUGUGGUCAGGCUGGGUGUGGGGGCUUAUGCCUGUAAUCCCAGCAAUUUGGGAGGUGGGGGUGGGCAGAUCAUUUGAGGUCAAGAGUUCGAGACCAGCCCAGCCAACAUGGUGAAACCCCAUCUCUACUAACAAUACAAAAAUUAGCUGGGUGUGGUGAUGUGCACCUGUAAUCCCAGCUACUUGGGAGGCUGAAGCAGGAGAAUCACUUGAACCUGGGAGGUGGAGGUUGCAUUGAGCCAAGAUUGCACCACUGCACUCCAUGCUGGGUGACAGGGUGCGACUCUGUCAAAAAUAAAUAAAUUAAAUUAAAUAAAUGUGGUAUUUGUAUUUAUUGCUUUUCCAAUGUUACAUCAACCUUGUAUUCCUGGAUAAGCUCGACUGUGACAUAAUGGAUCACUUAAAAAUACUUCAUGACCUUUACUAAUAUGUUAUGGAGCUAUGUUUGAAUAACAUUGUGAUUUUUAAAAAAUUGUCCCUUAAUGAUAUUUGUAUAUAAUGACUGUCAUAUACUGUAGUGGGGCAUGUUCCUACUAUUUCUAAAUUCUUAAUCUAUAAGAGUCAUCUAGGUUGGGAAUAGUGGCUCAGGCCUGUAAUCCCAGCACUUUUGGAGGCUGAGGCAAAAAGAUCCCUUGAGCCAAGGAGUUCAAACCAGCCUGGGCAACAUAGCGAAACCACAUCUCUAUUUAAAAAUACUACAAGAUAUUUUCAUUUUUUUGGUUUGUUUCUUUGUUUUUGAGUUGGUGUUUGUUUCUUUGUUUUUGAGUUAGUGUUUCACUCGUUGCCCAGGCUGGAGUGCAAUGGUGUGAUCUCAACUUACUGCAAAUUCCACCUCCUGGGUUCCAGUGGUUCUCCUGCCUCAGCCUCCCGAGUAGCUGAGAUUACAGACAGCCUCCACCUUGCCUGGCUGAUUUUUGUAUUUUUAGUAGAGACGGUUUCAUCAAGUUGGCCAGGCUGGUCUCAAACUCCUGACCUCAGGUGAUCUGCAUGCCUCAUACUCCCAAAGUACUGGGAUUACAGGCACAAGCCACUGUGCCCGGCCAAUACUGCAAAAUAUUUUAAAAAGUUAAAAUUAUCUCUUCUGGCUGGUCAUAGUGGCUCACACUUUUAAUCCCAGCACACUGGGAAGCUCAGUCAGAAGGAUUCCUUGAGGCCAGGAGUUCAAGAUCAGUCUGGGCAACACAGACCCCAUAUCUCCAAAAAAAUAAAAAUAAAUAAAUAAAACAGUUAUCAGGCUGGGAGUGGUGGCUCAUGCCUGUAAUCCCACCACUUUGGGAGGCUGAGGCAGGCAGAUCAUGAGGUCAAGAGAUCAAGACCAUCCUGGCCAACAUGUUGAAACCCCGUCUUUACUAAAAAUACAAAAAUUAGCUGGGCACGGUAUUGUGCCCCUGUAAUCCCAGCUACUCAGGAGGCUGAGGCAGGAGAAUCUCUUGAACCCCUGAAGUGGAGGUUUCAAUGAGCCUAGAUCACACCACUGCACUCCAGCCUGACGACAGAGCGAGAAUCCGUCUCAAAAAAAAAAAAAAAGACAACUAGGUUGGGCACGGUGCUUCACGGCUUUAAUCACAGCACUUUGGGAGGUCAAGGCAGGGGGUCACCUGAGGUCAGGAGUUCGAGACCAGCCUGGCCAAUGCGGUGAAACUUUUGUCUCUACUAAAAAUUCAAAAAAUAAAAUUAGCCAGGUGAGUUGGCGGGCGCCUGUAAUCCCAGCCGCUUGGGAGGCUGAGGCAGGAGAAUUGCUUGAAUCUGGGAGGCGAAGGUUGCAGUGAGUUGAGUUCUUGCCACUGCACUCCAGCCUGGGUGACAAGAGCAAAACUCCAUCUCAUAAAAAAAAAAAAAAAAAGACAACUAAGGCUUGCAUAAGUAUUUUGAGAAUAUUCUUCUAGGCAUGUUUUUAUUUCCAAAUGUGUAGCAAAAAUUUAUACUUUUUAUAUUUUUCAUUUUUGCUGGUUGUAUAACUUCAGUCUCCUUUUGCAUUCUGGAAUAACUUAUUAAUUGUGCAUUCUUUCCCUUUGCUUGUGUUAAUCUUGGUAGAGAGUACCCAGGUUUAUGAAUUCUUUCAGAUAUUUCGCUUGAAAAAUCUACACUAUUUCUUGCAUGUUUUCUGUUCCACUAAUUCUGUUAGAUAUUUAUAUAGUUACAUCAGCUUGAUUUUCCUCUACUUCUUAGUCUUUCUGUAUGCUUUUUAAAAAAAUGUGUCUUUUUAUACAUACUUUAGCUGGAGUUUUAAAAAAUCUGUAUACCGCUGGGCAUAGUGGCUGAUGUCUGUAAUCACAGCACUUUGGGAGGCCAAGGCAGGUGAUCACCUGAGGUCGGGAGUUCGAGACCAGCCUGACCAACACUGAGAAACCCCAUCUCUACUAAAAAUACAAAAUUAGCUGUGCCUAGUGGUGCAUGCCUGUAAUGCCAGCUACUUGGGAGGCUGAGGCAGGAGAAUCAUUUGAACCCGGGAGGCAGAGGUUGCAGUGAGCCGAGAUCACGCCAUUGCACUGCAGCCUGGGCAACAAGAGUGAAACUCUGUCACAAAAAAAAAAAAAAAAAGAAAAAAUACUUGAAUAAUACCAAUUAACAAUCCUUUUAUGUUGCACAUUUAGUGCCUGACAUUUAAUUAGUAAUAAUUUGGAUUAAUUUCUAGCAUCUAAUUUUUUUUGUUUGUUUCAUUGUGUUCCCCUCUUUGUACUGAUGUGUAUUGAUCAUACCUUUAAUUUAUUUUAUUCUUGAUGUUUGAAAUUUGUAUGUUACUUUUCGUUGUUACCAUAAAUAACAAUUUUAAAUAUAAGUCUUCCUUAAUACCUUUUCUUUCUAACUAAGUGCACUACACUGUUUGAAUAAAGUGAUUCCCAUAUACACUUACUACACUUGGAGAGAGACCCAGAAGGAAGUGCAUUGUCACACAAGCUAUUAGACAGAUCUGGUGGCAGAAAGAAUAGGCUCCUUGACAGAGGCCCAGUGACACCCUGUGGUAGAUUACAGAUGUCUUGAGAUUACUCUCUGAAGGUGCAAUCUCUCUCCUUUUUAUGUGAGCCAGUCCUUGCUUUGACCAGUAGAAACCAGCACAACUUUGGUUUGCAAGUCCAUCCUCAAGAGGCUUCUGCUAAUUAAGUAGCUGCUGUUUUCAGCUAGUAAUUUUUGUGGCUGUUUAUUACACAGUAAAGGCCAACUGAUACACAUACCCCUUUGCCCACAAGCCAAUAAACUGUGGUUCUUCAGGACCCACUGGGAAAUCCUCCAGAACCAGGCCCACUCGUGUUAGCAGUAAAGAAUUCUGGGCCAGGCACAGUGGCUCAUGCCUUUAAACCCAGCACUUUGGGAGGCUGAGAUGGUUGGAUCACGAGGCCAAGAGAUUGAGACCAUUUUGGGCAACAUGGUGAACCCCCAUCUCUACUAAAAAUACAAAAAUUAGCUGGGUGUGGUGGCACUCACCUGUAGUCCCAGCUACUUGGGGGCUGAGAUGGGAGAAUCACUUCAACCUGGGAGGUGGAGGUUACAGUGAGCUGAUAUUGCGCCACGGCACUCCAGCCUGGUGACAGUGUGAGACUCUGUCUCAAAAAAAAAAAAAAAAUUCUGUCAAUGUUCACAGAGAGACUGGGCAUCUCCCACUAUGAGCUGCAAUGAGAAAAUCAAGAUUUGAAUUCGUAUUCCUCUGCUUAGGGACUCAGGAGGCCGGAAGUCAGCAGGACUGAAGGCCCAAAGAAACAGUUGAUGUUAUGAGCUGCAAGCAAGUUGCCAGCUGAUAUGGUUUGGCUGUGUCCCCACCCAAAUGUCAUCUUGAAUUGUAGCUCCCAUAAUCCCCAUGGUGUCGAGGGAGAGACCAGGUGGGAGGUAAUAGAAUCAUGGGGGGGGGUUUCCCCAUGCUGUUCAAGUAAUUCUCAUGCCUCAGUCAGCCAAGUAGCUGGGAUAAUAGGCGUGUGCUGUUUUUGUCACAGUGAGUAAAUCUCAUGAGGUCUGUCAGUUUUAUAAGCAGCUGUUCCCCUGGACAGGCUCUCUUGCCUUCUGCCAUAUAAGAUGUGCCUUUGCUCCUCCUUCACCUUCUGUCAUGAUUUUGAGGCCUCCCCAGCCAUGUGGAACUGUGAGUCCAUUAAACCUCUUUUUCUUCAUAACUUACCCAGUCUCGGCCAGGCACGGUGGCUCACACUGUAACAACAACAAGGAACACAGCACCUAAACUCACACUUUUUUAUUUUGGUAGAGAAGGUAUCUCACUCCAUUGCCCAGGCUGUCCUCAAACUCCUGAGCUAGAGUAAUCCUCUCUUCUGGGCCUCCCAAAGUGCUGGGAUUACAAGCAUGAGCCACCAUGCCCAGCCAGACAUCUUUACAUGACAUUUUCAAGGUCCAAUUGGUCCUAAUUCUCCAUAAAUCCUUUCAGAGUAUUAACAAUGAAGCAAAUCUUGCUAAAUCUUUUUAUGAUGCAGUACAAGAUGUAUAUAUGUAUCGUUUUUAUCACUGAUAAAAACAGUACAGUCAUUAAAAACUACAGAAUUAUAUUGGUAAUGAAUAUUGGUACAAAUUCACUAAGUAAGCCAGGUACGGUGGCUCACAUGCCUGUAAUCCCAGCACUUUGGGAGGCUGAGGCAGGUGGAUCACAAGGUCAGAUUGAGAUGAUCCUGGCUAAAACGGUGAAACCUUGUAUCUACUAAAACUAAAAAAAUAUAGCUGGGCGUGGUGGCAUGUGCAUGUAUUCCUAGCUACUCGGGAGGCUGAGGCAGGAGGUUACAGUGAACCGAGAUCACACCACUGCACUCCAGCCUGGGAUACAGAGUAAGACUGUCUCAAAAAACAAACAAACAAAAAAAUGCGCUAAGUAUAAUAGUAGCAACUGGGCAAAGUGGCUUAUGCCUGGAGUCUCAACACUUUGAAAGGAGGCAAAAGGAUUACUUGAGCUCAGGAGUUCGAGACCUGCCUGGACAGCAUAGCAAGCCCCCCAUCUACAAAAAACUUAAAAAUUAAAAAAUGCAGUGAGCCAAGAUCAUGCCACUGCAUUCCAGCCUGGGCAACAGAGCAAGACUCCAUUUAAAAAAAAAAAAAAAAGAAGGAAAAAAGGAAGCUAGGAAGGAACGGAUUAGCAAAUAAAUUCCAACUGCUUGAUAAGAAAAUAGUAAACCCAGUGGCAUUUACUGCAGGAAUAUAAGGUUGGCUCUGGCUCAUUCGUAUCUUUGUAUUUGUGCAUUCAUCAUUAUGGAUGAUGCCUGGAAUUUGCCCAGAGGGAUGCUCAAGACCCUUUCAGACACAUUUUUUUUUUCUAAACUUAUUUAUUUAUGAAUGACAGAGUCUCGCUCUGUCACCCAGGCUGGAGUGCAGUGGCGUGAUCUCAGCUCACUGCAACCUCCAAUUCCUGGGUUCAAGUGAUUCUCCUGCCUCAGCCUCCCAAGUACCUGGGAUUACAGGUGUGCACCACCACACCCAGCUAAUUUUUGUAUUUUCAGUAGAGGCGGGGUUUUGCCAUGUUGGCCAGGAUGGUCUUGAACUCCUGAGACCCCCCUGAUUCAGCCUGAUUCAACCUCCCAAAGUGCUGGGAUUACAGGAAUGAGCCACAGUGGCCGGUGGUGUUCUUUUUUUUUUUUUUUUUUUCCAGAGACAGUGUCUUGCCAUGUCACCUAGGCUGGAGUGCAGUGGUGCAAUCAUAGCUCACUGCAGCCUCGACCUCCUGGGCUCAAGCAAUCCUCUCACCUCAGCCUUCUGAGUAGCUGGGAAUGCAGGCAUGUACCACCAGGCCCGGCUAAUUUUUUUAUUUUUAAAUUUUUUUUUUUUUGGUCGAGACUGUGUCUCACUAUAUUGCCCAGGCUGGUCUUGAAAUCCUGUUCAAGUUAUCCUUCUGCAUCAGCCUCCCAAAAUGCUAGGAUGACAGGGUUGAGCCACUGUGCCUGGCCUCUAUUUCUAAUGUCUAGGCAGCAACUGUUGUUGUGUUGUUCCUGUUACAUAGUCUUAUUACCCAUUUGAUACAAAGUUCAGAUUGAUUGUUCCUGUUCGUAUUCCAUUUUGGGUUUUCCCUCUAUCUUUGUUGAUUUUUUAAAAAAUUAAAUAUGUAAAAGAAUAAAGGGCCAAGCAGAGUGGCUCACAGUUGUAAUGCCAACAAUGUGGGAGGCCAAGGAAGGAUGAUCGCUUGAGCUCAGGAGUUUGAGGGCAGCCUAGGCAACAUAGAGAGAUCUCUUCUCUACAAAAUAUAUUUUUAAAAAUUAGCUGGAUGUGGUGGUGCACGUAUGUAGUCCCUGGUACUCAGGCAAAGGACUGCUUGAGCCCAGGAAGUAAAGGCUGCAGUGAGCCAUGAUAAUGCCACUAUACUUCAGCCUGUGUGACAGAGUGAAACCCUGUUUUUUUUUUUUUUUUUAAAGAAAAAAAAGAAUGUAAUUUUAAACAUCAGAACUGUAAGGUACUCUGAGCUGGCCAUACCAUGGUCAAGCCAUUGUGACAUCCCCCCGCCCUUGUGAUAAUGUACUUUGUGAUAUUCCCCUGCCCUUGUGAAUGUACUUUAUAAGAUACAUCCUCCCCCACCUAGUGAAUGUACCCUGCCAUUGGCCCUUGUGACAGUACACCUUUCCUCUCCUUGUAAAUGUACUUUGUAACCUUCCUCCCCACCCUUGUGAUGAUACACCCUCCCCGCCCUUGUGAAUGUACUUUGUAACAUCCUCCCCGCCCUUGAGAAUGUACUUUGUAACGUCCACCCCACUGCCUACAAAAAAAAUUGCUCCUAACUCCACCGCUUAUCCCAAACCUAUGAGAACUAAUGAUAAUCCCACCACCCUUUGCUGACUGUUUUGUUGGACAGCCCAUCCACAUCCGGAUGUAAUACACAGCCAUUGUUGCUCGCA